AGUUCCCUGGAGGCUUUUUGAUACUGAUUCGCGUACACCUGUUGUUUGAAAGCUCUCAGCGGGACAAUGCUGACCCAGCUGAAAGCAAAAUCAGAGGGGAAGCUUGCAAAACAGAUUUGCAAAGUUGUGUUGGAUCAUUUUGAAAAACAGUAUUCCAAAGAACUCGGAGAUGCCUGGAAUACAGUAAGGGAGAUACUAACAUCUCCAUCAUGCUGGCAAUAUGCUGUCCUGCUUAACCGAUUCAAUUAUCCUUUUGAACUGGAAAAGGAUUUACAUUUGAAGGGCUAUCACACACUCUCUCAGGGAUCUUUACCCAACUAUCCUAAAUCAGUGAAGUGUUACCUUAGCAGAACUCCGGGCCGAAUCCCUUCAGAAAGACACCAAAUUGGAAACCUGAAAAAAUAUUAUCUCCUAAAUGCUGCUUCUCUUCUCCCAGUGUUGGCUCUGGAAUUAAGGGAUGGGGAGAAGGUUCUGGAUCUCUGUGCUGCUCCUGGAGGGAAAUCAAUAGCUCUGCUGCAGUGUGCUUGUCCAGGUUAUCUUCAUUGUAAUGAAUAUGAUAGUCUGAGAUUGAGGUGGCUAAGGCAGACGUUGGAAUCUUUCAUCCCACAGCCUUUGAUAAAUGUAAUUAAAGUGUCUGAAUUGGAUGGCAGAAAAAUGGGAGAUGCCCAGCCUGAAAUGUUUGACAAGGUGUUAGUGGAUGCUCCGUGUUCAAAUGAUCGAAGCUGGUUGUUUUCUUCUGACUCUCAGAAGGCAUCCUGUAGGAUAAGUCAAAGGAGGAAUUUGCCUCUUCUACAGAUAGAGCUGUUAAGGUCUGCAAUUAAGGCCUUACGUCCUGGAGGGAUACUUGUAUACUCUACAUGCACGCUUUCCAAGGCAGAAAAUCAAGAUGUGAUCAGUGAAAUUUUAAACUCCCACGGUAACAUCAUGCCUAUGGACAUUAAAGGAAUAGCAAGGACUUGCUCCCACGACUUCACAUUUGCUCCCACUGGCCAGGAAUGUGGGCUCUUAGUGAUUCCAGAUAAGGGCAAAGCCUGGGGCCCAAUGUAUGUAGCCAAAUUGAAGAAAUCAUGGAGCACAGGAAAAUGGUGACAUGAAUUUGUAAACUGUGUUUAUGUGUUAUUAUAUUUAUAUUUCUGAACUCAGUACAUGUUAAUAUUUAAAUAAUUAUGCAGUAACUUUCUCUGGGUCUGUUUGGAAUCCUAUUUAGUUAAUACUUUAGCAUCUUAGAAUCUAGGCUUGAGAAUUGUUCAGGUGUAUUUUUUUCCUAGAAAUAUAUCUGUAACAAUGAUUUAAGGUGGUGCAGAUGGUGUUUGUUCUAUAUUAUAAAUCUGCUGUCUUUGCUUGGCAUUUUAUAGUUAAAUUAAUUAGAAUAUGUGGUUUUAUGCAUAACGUGUUUAGUUCUGUAUUCUUUCUAUGAUAGUGCUUUGAACCUUCAAAAAUUCACAUUUUCCAGCGCUCCGACCAUUUUCCCGCUUAUCAAAUGUACAAAUUUGUUCAAGGUUUUUUUUUCCCCCCAACUUUUGUAACUGAUUGUCUCAGAACUGAUUGGUAUUCUGAGACUAACUUUUUAAGCAGCACUAUUUCUAGUUCUGGCAAAAUAGUUUUUUUAUUUGCAAUGUUGUUUUCUGUUAAAGACUAUAUUAUGUUUACUGCAAAGGUCAGUGACUCUACUGACACCAGCUUUAUUUCCCCCACUUUUUUUGCAUUCACAAAUACAAAUUGAAAGGGUAAAUUAUAUUGAAAGGCCUUUAGAACAGCAGAUUCACAUGCACAUGUUUGACUUUCGACAUUCAGCUUAUAGAAUUAUGGAGUCUAUCCAGCAGGCUAUAAAGCAAGUACUUGAGACAAAACCGGAAUGAUUAAUAACUGCAAUCACUGAACUAUAUUUGGAGAGUUUUGUUACAUAAUUGCAGUCAUAAUGAGCACUACAGAAUCUGAUUAUCUUACAUUCACAAUCUGGAGGGGCUUUUUAUUUCACUUUGUUAUAAAAUGUUCUCUGAGAAUAUGAUGCCACAUAUUAAUGCACAAGAGGGAGAUGCCUAAUGAGAGUGGACUGUGUGAUUACCAGAACCCAGUGCCAUUUACUAAGUGGCUCUCCAUGUUUACAUAAAUCCUGGGAAUACUGUAUACAUUUCUUCUUAUGUACUUAGGGUUUUAGCUUCAGUCAGCAUCACACUUUUUCUCCAGAAAUUACUUCACUUAGAGUACAAACAUAUUUUUCCAACUAUUAAGAAAAAUUAUGCAGCACAUCUCAAAAAAUAGCAUCUCUUUGGAAAAUAGCCUUUAAAAAAAAACAACUUUAUCUGAUUAUAGAAAUACAAAAUUCUGCUAAAGCUGAAUACUUUUGAAUUGUUCAUUAUGUUCUGUGCCUUUAAACUAGAGACUAUUUGCUUAUUAAUAUUUUUUGUUUUGCAAGCAUAUGUAACCCGGUUUAUAUCAUCAGGAAGUCUUAGGAAGAAUUUUUUUUUCUGUACCUUCAGUCUGUUAAUCAUUUGUUUUCCUUUAUGUCCAAUUGAUAUGUUUAAAGUAAAGCUAAAGUCCAGGCACGGUGGCUUAUGCCUGUAAUCCCAGCACUUUGUCAGGCCGAGGCAGGGGGCAUCUCCUGAGGUCAGAAGUUCGAGACUAGCCUGCCCAACAUGGUAAAACCCCGACUCUACUAAAAAUGCAAAAAAAUUAGACAGGCAUGGUGGCUGGCACCAGCAAUCCCAGCUACUUAGGAGGCUGAGGCAGGAGAAUCACUUGAACCCAGGAGGCAGAGGUUGCAGUUAGCCAAGAUCUCGCCAUUGCACUCCAGCCUGGGCGACAAGAGUGAAACCCCGUAGCAAAAAAAUAAUAAUAAUAGUAAUUAAAUAAAAAUAAAGUAACGCUAGAACUGUUGGACCAAAUCAAGUAUAUGGGUAAAUACAGAAGAAUAAUGAUGGUGGAAAAGAUGUUUUCUUUUUUAAGUUAUCAUUAUUAGUUUGUUUUUUUUAUCUUCAGACACUAUAGGUUUUAAAAAUAGGUUUCUUUUAUGUAGGUUAAUCACAGAGUAAAUCUGCACACUGUACUUUGUUAAAUGUCGGUAUUUUCCCAGUAUAAUGCGAUGAAGCUUAAUCUGAAUACUUGGUAUGCUAUUGAAUUUACUUUCCUAUGAUUACUGAAAAAUGGAUGCACGUGUGUGUGUGUGUGUGUGUGUGUGUGUGUAUAUAUAUAUAUAUAUAUAAUUUUAUUAAAAGCAAUUGCCCCAAAAGCAGAAAUUGACAAGCGGGACCUAAUUAAACUGAAGAGCUUCUGCACAGCAAACUAAACUAUCAACAGAGUAGCAGACAACUUACAGGAUGGGAGAAAUAUUUGCAAAUUAUGCAUCUGCCAAAGGUCUAAUAUCCAGAAUCUAUAAGGAACUUAAAUCAGCAAGCAAAAAACAAAUAACCCUAUUAAAAACUGAGCAAAGGACAUGAACAGACAUUUCUCAAAAGAAGACAUUCACAUGGCCAACAAACAUAUGAAAAAGUGCUCUUCAUCACUAAUCAUCAGAGAAAUGCAAAUCAAAACCACACUGAGAUAAUAUUUUACACCAGUCAGAAUGGCUAUUAUUAAAAAGUCAAUAAAAUAAAAAAUAACAGACGCUGAUGAGGCUGUGGAGAAAAGGAACUGCUUAUGAACUGUUGGUGGAAAUGUAAAUUACUUCAGCCUCUAUGGAAAGCAGUUUGGAGAUUUCUCAAAGAACUUUAUAACAGAAUUGCCAUUUGAGCUAGCAAUCCCAUUAGUGGGUAUAUACCCACAGGAAAAUAAAUUGUCCUACAAAAAAAGACAUAAACGCUUGUGUGUUCAUCACAGUAAUAUUUACAAUAGUAAAGAUACGGAAUCAACCUAACCGCCCAUCAGCAGUUGAUUGAAUAAAGGAAAUGUGGUACAUAUACCUCGUGUAAUAUUACACAGUGAUAAAAAAGAAUGAAAUAAUGUCUUUUGCAACAACAUGGAUGCAGCUGGAUGCUUUUAUCCUAAGCAAAUUCAGGAACAGAAAACUAAAUACAUAUUCUCACUUACAAAUGGGAGCUAAAUAUCGAGUACACAUGGACAUAAAGGAACAAUAGACACUGGUGACUACUAGAGUGGGGAGGGGAGGAGGGGGAUGUAGGCUGAAAAACUACCUAUUGGGUACUGCACUCACUACCUGGGUGACGGGAUCGUCUGUACCCCAAACCUCAGCAUCAUCCAGUAUACCCAUGUAACACACCUGUUCAUGUAUCCCCUGAAUCUAAAAAGCUGAAAUUAUUUUUUAAUGAGAAGAUAAACCAUAAUUAUAAUGAAAUAGGUAAUAUUGAGCAUUGAAUAUUCUAUAAAUUGUUUAUAUAUGUUGUCUUUUUUUUUUUUUUUUUUUUUUUUUGAGACAGAGUCUUGCUCUGUCGCCCAGGCUGGAUGGCGUGCAGUGGCAUGAUCUCAGCUCACUGCAACCUCUGCCUCCCGGGUUCAAGCAGUUUUCUGCCUCAGCCUCCCAAGUAACUGAGAUCACAGGCACCCGCCACCAUGCUUGGCUAAUUUUUUUUGUAUUUUUAGUAAAGAUGGGGUUCCACCAUCUUGGCCAGGUUGAUCUUGAACUCCUGACCUUGUCAUCCACCUGCCUCAGCCUCCCAAAGUGCUGGGAUUACAGGCGUGAGCCACCACACCCACUGUGUAUGUUGUCUUUAUUGAUGCUUAAAACAAACUCAGGAAUAAGUAUUAUAACCCCCUUUUGUGAAUGAGAAAACCAAAGCUCAGUUCUGUUUAUAGUUUGCCAAGGCUACACUGGUAAGUAAAGGGUUCAGCCAAUGUAUAGACAGACUGUAUAGAUAUAUGAAGUGGGGGUGGGGGCCAAGGAGCUAUUACUGCUGUUUGGAAAUACUUGCCUCUUGUAGAUCCAGCUUUAACAUUUUUAUGACAUCCUAGUAAUAGCAGACCCUGCACAAAGUGGAUAUCAGAGUUAAUACUGUGAAGAGACAAAAUAAUGAGAAUACUUUUACCAAAGAUAAUGAAAUCUUGCAUAAUGUCUGCAUUUUUCCAUUGAUUGGAGUGCAUCCUUAGAAAACUGAAAAUAACAAAAACCCAGGACAUUUUUGGAAAUUGUAUGCUCUCUAGCAACUUUGCGUGAAUUUUUAUACAAACACUUAUGAGUUAUAUAAAAUGUUCUAAAACUAGAAAAAACAUGGUCUUGUAACAUGUUAUUUUCUUAGAUCACUGGUUUCUCAGAACAUGUCUUUCUGCAUGGCCUCCUCAUCCCCAUCCCAGGGGAGAACGUGAAUGUUCCAAGGGACUUCGGCCUCUGGGGCUUCCACACUCUGGGUGUCAGGGGUACAGCUCACAGGCUUUCAGUUUGGCCACAGCUGAAUGAUUGAGAAUUACCAGAUAAAUCCUCCAAAUCCAUUUCUCCAGAAACCUCUUCCUAGCCACACAGUGGGAGCCUUGUUUGACCUUUUUUAACCUUUCCUGGUCAGGUGCCAGGCCAGUCCUGCAAAGCCAGCAAAGUUUCAUUUUCAUUCAACCCUUUUUUUUUCACUUUGAAUCAAAUGGAAUUUAGUUCCUCCCACUGUCCCCAACCCAGCUAGAGUGCAGUGGUGUCAUCAUGGCUCACUGCAGCCUCGACUUCCUGGGUUCAAGUUAUCUUUUCGCCUCAGCCUCCUAAGUAGCCUGGACUACAGGCCCACAAUACCAUGCCUGGCUAAUUUUUAAAUUAUUAUUAUUAUUAUUAUUGUAGAGAUGUGACCUCACCAGGCUGGUUUCAAACCCCUGGCCUCAAGUGAUCCUCCCACUUCAGCCUCCCAAAGUAUUGGGAUUACAGGUGUGAGCCAUUGUGCUCGGCCUCAUAUAUUAUUAGUUGUAAAAAAGGAUGCAUGUUUUCCCUCACCUUCUCUUUGGCUAAUUAUAAAUCAUUUUACUUAAUAUUUCAUAGUUAAAGGGUAGAGCCGCGAUCAAAACUGGCUCCGAGGUCCAGGCCCUUUUCCCAACACUAUGCUGUCUCACAGAGUGUAGGUUGUUUGAACCCUCAAGAUUAUUAACUGACUUUACCCCUAUUUUCCAUUGUUCAGUUUCCUCCUUUUGUGUCAUACCCUAUUCCCAGGGGAUGAAAGGAUUAAUCAAUACUUGGGAAAAAAACAACAACCUUUGAACUGUUUCAGGCCAUAUUGUAAAGAAGUGUGUCUUGUGAUUUUGAUACCCAGAAAUCUCCAGUGGAGGGUAUUCUCUGCCUUCCUUUUCUUUGCAGAUGCUGAGCUGAAGAAUGGAAAUUUGGAGCAGACUUGCAGUGUCAAUUGUAAAGCAAAGAGUAAUUGAUAUUACUUUCUGUGACACUGAGUUACUUUCAAAAUAGCUUUAUAAAAAUUUAGGUUGCUUACCAACACAUUAACUUCUCCCUGCCGUCCACACGCUGAACAGCCACUACUUUCAGAAAUAGACUGAAUAAAUGUAAUGCAUUUAAA